CGGGCAGCUCUGCCCGCCUCGCUAGCGGCACUGCCCGGCUGGGUCUGGGGAGCCUCGUGUCGCGCUGCCGCGCCGAGGCUUCCGGCACGGGCGGGAACGACAGUCCCAGAGUUCCCCGCGGCGGGGGCGGAAGCCGGGGCGGGGCGGGCUCAGGACCCCCGACAGCCGGUCCCUGGAGAUCUGAGGGGCCGGGGCGGGCUCAGGGAUGCCUCGCGCCCGCGGAGAGACGGGCCCGGGACUUGGGAAGAGCAAGCUCCGGGAUCCAGCUCGGGCGCUGCUGGGUUCAGCGCCCGAGCUGGGCUUUGCAGGCUGAGCCGCGAGCCACUUGUUUGUGGGGAGAAUUUACACCCGCGACGAGUUCGAGCUUGAAGGCUCCCGCUGGGCUUGGGCUGCAUGGAGCGGGGUCCAGCGCUGCCUGGCGGCUUCACGCGAACCCUGGGCGCGUCCCUUGCGGAGGUGCCGGUGCCUCCCUCUGCAGAGACCAGGAGAGAGCCUCUGGGCGUUGGGCGGUGUUGCCCAGCUGGGACGAUGCCGGAGUGUGAAGGAGUUUGAGAAGCUGAACCGCAUUGGAGAGGGUACCUACGGCAUUGUGUAUCGGGCCCGGGACACCCAGACAGAUGAGAUUGUCGCACUGAAGAAGGUGCGGAUGGACAAGGAGAAGGAUGGCAUCCCCAUCAGCAGCUUGCGGGAGAUCACGCUGCUGCUCCGCCUGCGUCAUCCGAACAUCGUGGAGCUGAAGGAGGUGGUUGUGGGGAACCACCUGGAGAGCAUCUUCCUGGUGAUGGGUUACUGUGAGCAGGACCUGGCCAGCCUCCUGGAGAAUAUGCCAACACCCUUCUCGGAGGCUCAGGUCAAGUGCAUCGUGCUGCAGGUGCUCCGGGGCCUCCAGUAUCUGCACAGGAACUUCAUUAUCCACAGGGACCUGAAGGUUUCCAACUUGCUCAUGACCGACAAGGGUUGUGUGAAGACAGCGGAUUUCGGCCUGGCCCGGGCCUAUGGUGUCCCAGUAAAGCCAAUGACCCCCAAGGUGGUCACUCUCUGGUACCGAGCCCCUGAACUGCUGUUGGGAACCACCACGCAGACCACCAGCAUCGACAUGUGGGCUGUGGGCUGCAUACUGGCCGAGCUGCUGGCGCACAGGCCUCUUCUCCCCGGCACUUCCGAGAUCCACCAGAUCGACUUGAUCGUGCAGCUGCUGGGCACGCCCAGUGAGAACAUCUGGCCGGGCUUUUCCAAGCUGCCACUGGUCGGCCAGUACAGCCUCCGGAAGCAGCCCUACAACAACCUGAAGCACAAGUUCCCAUGGCUGUCGGAGGCCGGGCUGCGCCUGCUGCACUUCCUGUUCAUGUACGACCCUAAGAAAAGGGCGACGGCCGGGGACUGCCUGGAGAGCUCCUAUUUCAAGGAGAAGCCCCUACGUCUUCCGAUCAGUGGUGUCUGUGAAGGGUGCCGCGAGCCAGGCUGACCAGGCGCCCGGGAUCCAGCUCAUCCCCUUGGCUGGGAACAUCCUCCACUGACUUCCUCCCACUGUCUGCCCUGAACCCACUGCUGCCCCCAGAAAAAGGCCGGGUGACACCGGGGGGCUCCCAGCCCGUGCACCCUGGAAGGGCAGGUCUGGCGGCUCCAUCCGUGGCUGCAGGGGUCUCAUGUGGUCCUCCUCGCUAUGUUGGAAAUGUGCAACCACUGCUUCUUGGGAGGAGUGGUGGGUGCAGUCCCCCCGCUGUCUUUGAGUUGUGGUGGACGCUGGCCUGGGAUGAGAGGGCCCAGAAGACCUUCGUAUCCCCUCUCAGUCGCCCGGGGCUGUCCCGUGCAUGGGUUGGCUGUGGGGACCCCAGGUGGGCCUGGCAGGACUCCAGAUGAGGACAAGAGGGACAAGGUAUGGGGUGGGAGCCACAAUUGAGGAUACCCCGAGACUACCAGGAGAGCCCUGGGCUGGAGGCUGAGCUGCAUCCCUGCUCCCCACAUGGAGGACCCAACAGGAGGCCGUGGCUCUGAUGCUGAGCGAAGCUAUAGGCUCUUGUUGGAUAAAAGCUUUUUUAACAGA